GCUGUGCAGGGCAGGGAAGCUCCAGGCAAACAGCCCAGCAAACAGCAGCACUCAGCUAAAAGGAAGACUCACAGAACACAGUUGAAGAAGGAAAGUGGCGAUGGACCUCAUCCCAAAUUUGGCGGUGGAAACCUGGCUUCUCCUGGCUGUCAGCCUGGUGCUCCUCUAUCUAUAUGGGACCCGUACACAUGGACUUUUUAAGAGACUGGGAAUUCCAGGGCCCACACCUCUGCCUUUGUUGGGAAAUGUUUUGUCCUAUCGUCAGGGUCUCUGGAAAUUUGACACAGAGUGCUAUAAAAAGUAUGGAAAAAUGUGGGGAACGUAUGAAGGUCAACUCCCUGUGCUGGCCAUCACAGAUCCCGACGUGAUCAGAACAGUGCUAGUGAAAGAAUGUUAUUCUGUCUUCACAAAUCGAAGGAUUUGUGCAACGACCAGCACCAUCAAGAUGCAGACCCAUUCCGUCACCAUGUGGCUCCCUCCUGCUGUCCUACAGUCACAACAUGGAGUUUGUCUUUUUCUCUGACAGGUUCUAUAUCAGAGCAAACUUUUAUUUAUUUGAGGAGGCCAAUGUAUUAAUAUUUCCUUUUAUGGAUUGUUCUUUUGGUGUUAAGUCUGAAAAUCCUUUGCUUAGCCCUCCUUCCUACAUUGCUUUUUCUAAGAGUUAUAUAGUUUAACACUUUACAAAAUGUAACUCUAUUACCCAUUUUGUGUUAAUAUUUGCAUAAGUUAUGAGAUUUAGAUCAAGGUUCAUUUUCUGUGGACUAUGGCUGUCCAAAUGUUCCAACACCAUUUUGGAAAGGUAGGCAUAUUGUCAAAACUCAGCUGAGUAUAUUUUGUGAAUCUAUUUCUUAUUGUUUACUCCUCCACUAAUACCACACUGUGGUGACUCUAGUAGCUGUACAGUAACUCUUAACAUCAUAUAGGGCAAUUCUUUCCACUUUAUUGAUUUAUAUUUUCAGAAUGGCUUUAGCUUUUCUUGUCCCUUGCCUUUCCAUAAAAAUUCAGAAUAAGCUUGUAAGUGUCUACAAACAAACCUGCCAUAAUUUUGAUAAGAAUUAAAGCAGAGGUGUCCAAUCUUUUGGCUUCCCUGGGCCACAGUGGAAGAAGAAGUGUCGUGGGCCACACAUAAAAUACACACACACACACACACACACACACACACACACACACACACACACAAAUGGUCUGUGUAUAGUUUUCAUUAUAUAUCUACCACCACAGAUAAGCAAAAAUGUCCUUGCAUAAUAAUCCUAAUUAUGCACUGCCCCAUUCAGAGGGUCUUUCAAAAUCAUUGAACAGGUUCCAAGUUUGCAAUCACUGAUACAGAAAAUGUACAUAUCUAGCUAAACUUCACUACUUUUUUGAUAUUUUUUAUUAUAAAAGAAAAGAGAACAACAUAAAACUAGUGGGGUACUUGACAUUGUUUUUGAGAAACUAAUCCAUCAGUAUCUGGCUUGAUGGAAGUAGUUGCAAUUCUCAGUGAGUUCUCAAGGUGCUCAUCAGAUAUUUUGGUUCUAAUUUUACUCUUCGUGUUCUUCAUCCUUGAAAAUAGUAGCUCACAAAUGUAAGUGCUGCCAAAAAGCAAUGACAUGAACAAGGUGUGAUUGUGAAGCAAGGGAUAUUUGUCAUUGGGAAGACAGGUCUUACAAAAGUCCAGUAAAGAGGCAAAAUCAAAUUUUUCUAUAAGUUGAACAUCAGAUUGCAGCUCUAGGCAUUCCAUUUCAAAAUUGCCAGGUAACAUAUAUAUGUCGACUGAAAAUGGAGUUGCAAAUAUACCAAAAUAUUGAUGAUUUUUUCAGAAAUCUUGAAAUACCUGUUUUCAAAUUCCUGUAUCAAAUUGAAAAGCAAGGCUGCGUAUUUUUGGCUGUUCACAGGACCAUGUUUAGCCAACAUGUCGAAAUGCAUAAAAUUGUUUGCCUUAAUUUGAGCUUGCCAUAAUUUCAGUUUCAUAUGGAAUGCUGUUAUGGUUUGAAACAUUGUAUUGUUAAGUUGGUUUUCAACUUGAAGACACAGGUUUAACUCACUUAAAUGGGCCGUCAAACCCACUAAAAAUGCUAAAUCUGUAAGCCAGUUUUCAUUGUCAAGUUCUGGCACCAAUUUUGUUUGAUACCAUAAACAGCUUGAUUUCACAUCACAAAGCAUAAAAUCUUUACAUUUUGCCUUGACUUAACCAUCUUACUUCUAAAAAGUGAAUGACUUGCUAGAGUCAGCAUCCAUACUUUUAAGGAAUUCCUGAAACUAGCGAUGAUUCAAUUCCUGGGCCCUUGUGAAAUUUACAGCCUUGAUGACAAUUUGCAUGACGUUAUCUACUUUUAAAGCUUGUGCACAUGGAUUUUCUUGAUGUAUUAUGCAAUAAUACUUCAUCAAAUGUGAGUUUUGUGUGGCAACUGCAUCAUCUAUUAAUUGUACAAGUCCCUCUCUUUUACCUACCAUCGCCAGGGCAGCAUCUGUAGCUAUAUCACAUAUGUUUACAAAGGACAAAGAAAAUUGCUUUAACAUAUUUUUCACUGCUUCAUAUAAAUCUCUUGAUUUAGUUGUGUCUUUUAAUAGCAUGGUGACAUUUCGAUUUCUUCAGUGACAUUAUAUUCAUCAUCAAUACCUCUAAUAAAAAUAGCAAGUUGUGCCGUAUCUGUAGUGUCAGUGCCUUCAUCCAUCACCAAAGCAUAAAAUUUUAAAUUAGCAGUUUUACUCUCCAAACGUCUUUCAAUAGAUUUCCCAAUUUCUCCAAUUCUCCUGGCUAUAGUCUGGUGAGACAAACUGAUUUUAGAAAUAUCAGUUUCUCAAGGCAAAUAAUAUCUACCACAUCUUCCAGACAUUGCUUAAUAAACUCACCAUCAGUAAAUGGUUUUGAUUUUUUUGCUAUUAAAUUUGCUACCACAUAACUAGGUUUUACCUUACGAUUGAGUCCGAGUUGUAACUUUUUAAAAAAUCUUUUUUGUUGAAAAGACAGACUUUUUUUCAGUUCUGCUAUUUUGUCCUUACAACACAUACACACCAAAUUUGUCAGCACGUUUUUGCAUAUAAUGCCUCUUCAAAUUGUAGUCUUUGAAAACUGGCACAAAUUCCGUGGAAAUUAAGCAGAGUGCUUCGCUAUUUGCCUCAACAAGAAAAAGUCAUUUGUCCACUUUUCAUUGAACAAUCUUCCUUCAUCCAUAAUUUUUGUUUUUUAGGGUUUUCUUUUUAAGACAUUGUGGAAGCCAUUCUGGAAUUAAAAGCAUUAUAAUAGAUAAGCAACUAUAUUUACUUUUAUUAUGGAAAUUAACAGAUAGGAAAAUAGAACAGAAAGCAAGGUUUAAUAAUCAAAUAAGAAUACUUACAUGUCUUCUAAAUAAUAUUAAACACCUAUCAUCUACAAAGGUAGGUUGAAAUAUUAUUGAUAAUUGCUGGGUUUUACUUGCCAAAUUGCCACAAACACACCUAAUACCUGACAGUGUCAAUUCAACUGUCCGUGAUUAGAAGAUAACACACUGGAAGUCGCACACCACCAUAAAACUGAAGCCACACAUGCGUACAAAUGGCGACAGUGUCUGGUGUACAGCAGCGCUCUGCCUUGUCCAGAAUACACACUUGAAUUCUUUGUCACAAUUCACUUCACGUGGCACUGCAAUAGCGUCCUCUCGCUCUUUGUUAGUUAAUUUUAAUGGCUUUUAAUUUCUUCUUGCUGAACUGUUUGCAAUUAUAAUGCAAAUUAUGGAUACUAGUCCAUUAUUUGUGGAUGUGACAUACUCUGAUUACCCCUUUCCAUUCCAUUGUUGUCUACGAAGUUCACACUUGAGAAUCACAUAGUCAAAUUACAAAAUUACAAAAAAAAUUGCAAAAAAACUCAAAAUGUUUUAAGAAAGUUUCCACAUUUGUAUUGGGAUACAUUCAAAGCCAUCCUGGACUGCAUGAGGCCUGCAGGCCACAAGUUGGACAAGCUUGAAUUAAACCAAUAGAACAAUUUGGGUAUAAUCUAUAUCUUUACUAUGUUCAGCCUUUCAUCCCGUGAAUAUAGUAUGCCUCUCCAUUUCUUUAGCUUUUAUUACUUUCCUCAACAUUUUAUAGUUUUCAGCAUAGAGGUCCUGUACAUCUUUUGUUAGAUUUACACCAGAAAUAUUUCAUUUUUGUUGGAGUAACUGUAAAUGAUACUGUUUUUCUUGUAUUUUCAGAUAUUGAUUAUUGUUACAUAGAAAUGUGAAUAAUUUUGUUUGUUGAUCUUGUAUCCUAUAGCCUUGCAGAACUUACCUAUUCGUUCUAGAAAUUUUUUUGUAUAUUCCUUGACAUUUUAUACAUUGACAAUUAUGUCACCUGAAAAUAGAGACAAUUCUAUUAUUUCCUUUCCAAUCUGUAUGCCUUUUAUUUCUUUUUCUUGUCUAGUGUAUUAAGACAUCAGGUAUGCUCUUUAGUAAGAAUGUUGAGAGUGGGCAUUUUUUAGUUCUUCUUGAUCUUGGAAAAACCAUUCAGUCCUUCAUCAUUAAAUGUGAUUUAACUGAA